GUUUCCUCCCAACAUGGCGGCCGGGGCAGGUCGGCGGUGAUGGGGGCCAGUUCGCGGCCGCGGCGGGUGCUAAUCCCCACAGUAGCCAGGGUAGCCCUUCUCUCGCGGUGCCUCUGAGAGCCGCCGCCACCUCGUCCCUCAGUUCCCGGCAGACAGCCGCCCGGGCCGGGCUCCCUCACCGCCACCAGGGCCGGAGGGACGAGUGAGAGGGGCGGCCGGGACGCGACCCCCGGGCCGGGAGAAGCGGAGGCCCGACGGGCGCGGCCCUCGAGGUACGGCUUCUUGGGGGCGGCGAGGACCUCGACGCCCUUCGCCGACACCGCGGCUGGUCCCGCUCGCCCGCCCCUUCCUGAUCCUGCCGCUGCCCUCCACGCCUCCAAUCCCCCACCUCCACCCCCUCUCCUUUCUCUCUUCUCUUCCUUCCUCUCCUCCUCCUCCCCUCCAGCCGCUGGGAGCCGCGGGUCGGACGAGCCGCCGCCUCCUUCUCUGCGUCCAUGUAUGAGGGGAAGAAGACGAAGAACAUGUUCCUGACCCGGGCUCUGGAGAAGAUAUUGGCCGACAAGGAAGUGAAGAAGGCGCAUCACUCCCAGCUGCGCAAAGCUUGCGAGGUGGCGUUAGAGGAAAUAAAAGCGGAAACUGAAAAACAGAGUCCUCCUCAUGGAGAAGCAAAAGCUGGAUCAAGCACCCUUCCACCAGUGAAAUCAAAGACAAAUUUUAUUGAAGCAGACAAGUACUUCUUGCCUUUUGAGUUGGCAUGCCAGUCCAAAUGUCCUCGCAUAGUUAGUACAUCUCUAGAUUGCUUACAGAAACUUAUUGCUUAUGGGCACUUGACUGGCAAUGCUCCAGAUAGUACAACACCAGGCAAAAAAUUAAUUGAUAGAAUUAUUGAAACAAUAUGUGGCUGCUUUCAGGGCCCUCAGACAGAUGAAGGAGUUCAGCUGCAGAUAAUAAAGGCUUUACUUACUGCAGUAACAUCACAACACAUAGAAAUUCAUGAAGGGACUGUACUGCAAGCUGUGAGAACAUGUUACAAUAUCUACUUAGCAAGCAAAAAUCUCAUCAAUCAGACAACAGCCAAAGCUACUCUCACUCAGAUGCUAAAUGUUAUCUUUGCACGCAUGGAAAACCAAGCAUUACAGGAAGCAAAACAAAUGGAAAAAGAAAGGCAUCGGCAGCAUCAUCAUCUGUUACAGUCUCCAGUAAGCCAUCACGAGCCUGAAUCACCUCAACUUAGAUAUUUGCCACCUCAGACUGUUGAUCAUAUAUCCCAAGAACACGAAGGGGACCUUGACCUCCAUACAAAUGAUGUAGAUAAAAGUCUUCAGGAUGACACAGAGCCUGAAAAUGGAUCUGAUAUUUCCAGUGCAGAAAAUGAACAGACUGAAGCUGAUCAGGCAACUGCAGCUGAAACAUUAUCUAAAAAUGAAGUGUUAUAUGACGGAGAAAACCAUGAUUGUGAGGAAAAGCCACAAGACAUUGUACAGAACAUUGUAGAAGAAAUGGUGAACAUUGUUGUUGGAGAUAUGGGAGAAGGGACUACUAUAAAUGCAAGUGCAGAUGGCAACAUUGGAACUAUAGAGGAUGGUAGUGACAGUGAAAAUAUUCAAGCAAAUGGAAUUCCAGGAACACCAAUUUCUGUUGCAUAUACACCAUCCUUACCUGAUGAUAGAUUGUCAGUCUCUUCCAAUGAUACUCAGGAAUCUGGAAAUUCUUCAGGACCUUCACCUGGUGCUAAGUUUUCCCACAUUUUACAAAAGGAUGCCUUUCUAGUAUUCAGGUCAUUGUGUAAACUGUCAAUGAAACCACUGUCAGAUGGACCACCAGAUCCAAAGUCUCAUGAACUACGAUCCAAGAUUCUUUCAUUGCAGUUACUUCUAUCCAUUCUGCAGAAUGCAGGACCUAUUUUCAGGACAAAUGAGAUGUUUAUUAAUGCUAUUAAGCAGUAUCUUUGUGUUGCACUCUCAAAAAAUGGAGUCUCAUCUGUUCCAGAGGUUUUUGAGCUUUCUCUUUCUAUAUUUCUUACUUUGUUGUCAAAUUUCAAGACACAUCUGAAGAUGCAAAUUGAGGUGUUCUUUAAAGAAAUUUUCUUAUACAUUUUGGAAACUUCUACCAGCUCAUUUGAUCACAAAUGGAUGGUUAUUCAGACACUGACGAGGAUUUGUGCAGAUGCUCAGAGUGUAGUGGAUAUUUAUGUAAACUAUGACUGUGACUUAAAUGCAGCCAAUAUAUUUGAAAGACUAGUAAAUGAUCUAUCAAAAAUUGCUCAAGGAAGGGGCAGUCAAGAACUUGGUAUGAGUAAUGUUCAGGAAUUGAGCCUGAGGAAAAAAGGUUUAGAAUGCUUAGUGUCGAUUUUGAAGUGUAUGGUUGAAUGGAGUAAGGAUCAGUAUGUGAAUCCCAACUCCCAGACAACUCUUGGUCAGGAAAAACCCUCAGAGCAAGAGAUGAGUGAAAUCAAACACCCUGAGACAAUAAACAGAUACGGAAGUUUAAAUUCCCUGGAGUCAACAUCAUCAUCAGGAAUAGGCAGCUACAGUACACAGAUGUCUGGCACUGAUAAUCCAGAACAAUUUGAGGUCCUAAAGCAACAAAAAGAAAUAAUAGAACAAGGGAUAGAUUUAUUUAAUAAGAAACCAAAGAGAGGAAUACAGUACCUCCAAGAACAAGGGAUGCUUGGCACCACACCUGAAGAUAUUGCCCAAUUCUUACAUCAAGAGGAAAGAUUAGACUCUACUCAAGUGGGUGAGUUCCUGGGAGAUAAUGAUAAAUUUAACAAAGAAGUCAUGUAUGCAUAUGUGGACCAACAUGACUUUUCAGGAAAAGACUUCGUUUCAGCCCUUCGUAUGUUUCUAGAAGGAUUUCGUCUUCCAGGGGAAGCUCAGAAAAUCGAUCGAUUAAUGGAAAAAUUUGCUGCAAGAUACCUAGAAUGCAACCAAGGACAAACUCUCUUUGCUAGUGCGGAUACAGCUUAUGUUUUGGCUUAUUCAAUUAUCAUGUUGACCACAGACCUUCACAGUCCACAGGUGAAAAAUAAAAUGACAAAGGAACAAUACAUUAAGAUGAAUAGAGGUAUCAAUGACAGUAAAGACCUUCCUGAAGAGUAUCUAUCAGCCAUCUAUAAUGAAAUAGCUGGGAAAAAGAUAUCAAUGAAAGAAACAAAAGAACUAACAAUCCCUACAAAAUCAAGUAAACAGAAUGUAGCCAGUGAAAAACAAAGAAGACUUCUGUAUAACUUAGAAAUGGAGCAGAUGGCCAAGACAGCUAAAGCACUCAUGGAGGCCGUGAGCCAUGUUCAGGCACCCUUUACAAGUGCAACACAUUUGGAGCAUGUGAGGCCCAUGUUUAAGUUGGCUUGGACGCCUUUUCUGGCUGCAUUCAGUGUGGGUCUACAAGAUUGUGAUGAUACUGAAGUAGCCUCUCUUUGCCUGGAAGGUAUAAGAUGUGCAAUCAGAAUUGCAUGCAUUUUCAGCAUUCAGCUGGAGAGAGAUGCAUAUGUCCAGGCACUAGCAAGAUUUACCUUACUCACAGUGAGUUCCGGUAUUACUGAAAUGAAACAGAAGAACAUUGACACAAUAAAAACACUUAUCACAGUGGCUCAUACAGAUGGAAAUUAUUUAGGAAAUUCAUGGCAUGAGAUUCUGAAGUGCAUCAGUCAGUUGGAGCUGGCACAGCUUAUAGGAACUGGAGUGAAACCUCGAUACAUUUCUGGAACAGUGCGAGGCAGAGAAGGAUCUCUUACUGGAACAAAAGAUCAGGCUCCUGAUGAAUUUGUGGGUUUAGGGCUAGUUGGAGGAAAUGUGGACUGGAAACAGAUAGCAAGUAUUCAGGAAUCCAUUGGAGAAACCAGUUCUCAGAGUGUUGUUGUUGCUGUAGAUAGAAUAUUCACAGGAUCUACAAGGCUAGAUGGAAAUGCCAUUGUGGAUUUUGUCCGUUGGCUCUGUGCUGUGUCUAUGGAUGAAUUACUUUCCACGACACACCCAAGAAUGUUUAGUCUACAAAAAAUAGUAGAAAUAUCAUAUUACAACAUGGGAAGAAUAAGAUUACAGUGGUCUCGAAUUUGGGAAGUUAUUGGAGAUCAUUUUAAUAAGGUUGGGUGUAAUCCUAAUGAAGAUGUAGCUAUUUUUGCAGUAGACUCCUUGAGGCAGUUGUCAAUGAAGUUCUUAGAGAAAGGGGAGCUUGCUAACUUCAGAUUCCAGAAGGAUUUCUUAAGACCUUUUGAACAUAUAAUGAAACGGAACAGGUCUCCAACAAUUCGAGAUAUGGUUGUACGGUGUAUAGCACAGAUGGUUAAUUCUCAAGCUGCUAACAUUCGAUCUGGAUGGAAGAACAUUUUCUCUGUAUUUCAUCUAGCUGCAUCUGAUCAAGAUGAAAGCAUAGUGGAACUUGCAUUCCAAACAACCGGGCACAUUGUCACCCUUGUAUUUGAAAAACACUUUCCAGCGACCAUUGAUUCUUUCCAGGAUGCAGUGAAGUGUUUGUCUGAAUUUGCGUGCAAUGCAGCUUUCCCAGACACAAGUAUGGAAGCAAUUCGACUUAUUCGCCAUUGUGCAAAAUAUGUGUCUGAUAGACCUCAGGCUUUCAAGGAAUACACAAGCGAUGAUAUGAACGUAGCACCUGAAGACAGGGUGUGGGUGAGAGGAUGGUUCCCAAUUCUCUUUGAGUUAUCCUGUAUCAUCAAUAGAUGCAAAUUAGAUGUAAGAACCAGGGGUUUAACAGUAAUGUUUGAAAUAAUGAAAACAUAUGGCCACACUUAUGAGAAACACUGGUGGCAGGAUUUAUUUAGAAUUGUUUUCAGAAUCUUUGACAAUAUGAAAUUGCCAGAACAACAGACAGAGAAAGCUGAAUGGAUGACAACAACUUGCAAUCAUGCACUUUAUGCAAUCUGUGAUGUAUUCACUCAGUAUUUAGAAGUACUCAGUGAUGUACUUUUGGAUGACAUUUUUGCUCAGCUCUACUGGUGUGUGCAGCAAGACAAUGAGCAGUUAGCGCGAUCUGGUACAAACUGUUUAGAGAAUGUUGUUAUUCUGAAUGGUGAAAAAUUUACCCUAGAAAUCUGGGAUAAAACUUGCAACUGCACACUGGAUAUCUUCAAAACCACAAUCCCACAUGCGCUGUUGACCUGGCGACCCAAUUCUGGAGAAACUGCCCCCCCACCUCCAUCUCCUGUAAGUGAAAAGCCAUUGGAUACAAUAUCACAGAAGUCUGUAGAUAUUCAUGAUUCUAUUCAACCAAGGUCUGUGGAUAACAGACCACAAGCACCACUGGUUUCUGCGUCUGCUGUUAAUGAAGAAGUCAGCAAAAUUAAAUCUACAGCAAAAUUUCCAGAACAAAAAUUGUUUGCUGCCCUGUUGAUUAAAUGUGUUGUGCAGCUGGAACUCAUCCAGACUAUCGACAACAUUGUCUUCUUCCCAGCCACAAGUAAGAAAGAAGAUGCAGAAAACUUAGCUGCAGCACAGAGAGAUGCGGUGGACUUUGAUGUUCGCGUUGAUACUCAAGACCAAGGAAUGUACCGCUUUUUAACAUCACAACAACUUUUUAAGCUACUGGACUGCUUAUUAGAGUCACAUAGAUUUGCAAAAGCGUUUAAUUCCAACAACGAACAGAGGACUGCCCUGUGGAAAGCAGGAUUCAAAGGCAAAUCCAAGCCCAACCUUCUGAAGCAGGAGACCAGCAGCCUGGCCUGUGGGCUGCGCAUUCUCUUCCGGAUGUACAUGGAUGAGAGCCGCGUUAGUGCCUGGGAGGAGGUCCAGCAGAGGCUUUUGAAUGUCUGCAGUGAAGCACUAAGUUACUUCCUCACUCUAACAUCAGAAAGUCAUCGAGAAGCCUGGACUAACUUACUGCUUUUGUUUCUAACUAAAGUUCUAAAGAUAAGUGAUAAUAGGACCAAACGGACCCUGUGAGCAUGGGGCUGCCAGUGAAAGGAGGAUGCCUGGGAAUGAAAUCAAUAGAAGAGAUGCAGAAAGCCUACGGAAAAACAGCGUGCUGAUACUAUUUGACACAGCAAUGAUUAUUUCUUACCUUUGGCACCUUCCUGCAUUUUUAUUCUGUUCAGCCUCUUCUGCUGCUCUCUUAGCAGGGCUUGCUGCUGAAUCUCUAAGGUGUGAUGAUCUCUUGGAGGAUCCAGGUACAUAAAUUUCAGAUCAACUCGUGUUUCUGAAUCUGGUAUAAAAAAUAUGUUAUAUAACUAAGUUAAAUGUUGUUUUCAAAUGGGAUUUUGUAAAACUUCACUGUAAGUAACAUGAGUAACCUAAUUUCAAAAUCAAGGAAAUGAUAGAAAUAGUGAAACAUCACUAAAGUCAAAGGACAGUAAAAUAGCCACAAAACUAAAGAAUAUGAAAUUAAUAUUCUUUAAUAAGUGUCUUUUCACAAACUUACCAACAUAAGGAAUACCCCAGAACAAGCAGUGGAUGUUGCAUUGUCCAUCUCUACCUGUCCUAGCCCUGCCAGGAUGCCACCCAGAACACAGACUACGUGCAGGUAUAUCCAAGCAGAUGGUCACAUGGCUAUGACUAAGGCAGCCAUGAGACACUGUAAUCACGGCUGAUCUCUAAAAUAUACUGGAAACGUGAAAAAAUAAUGUUACUGGCCAAUUAAUAUUUUAGUCCUUACAAAUAUCAUGCAGAAAGCAAGAUAAAUGUAGACUGGCUGGAACUUGAGGGGGAAUGCCAUUUCUUUUUUUUUUUUUUUCUUGAGACGGAGUCUUGCUCUGUCGCCCAGGCUGGAGUGCAGUGGCACGGUCUUGGCUCACUGCCAGCUCUGCCUCCUGGGUUCAUGCCAUUCUCCUGCCUCAGUCUCCCAAGUAGCUGGGACUACAAGCACCCACCACUAUGCCCGGCUAAUUUUUCUUGUAGUUUUUAGUAGAGACGAGGUUUCACUAUGUUGGCCAGGCUGGUCUUGAACUCCUGACCUCGUGAUCCACACGCCUCGGCCUCUCAAAGUGCUGGGAUUACAGGCAUUAGCCACUGUGCCUGGCCAAGAAUAAAAAUUUUUUAAUCUUGAGAAGAAACAUACAGUUCAUACAUAUAAAAAGCCUUGAAAAUAUUAUUCCCUUUGACUCACUAAUUACACUGCUGGAAUAUAAAGAAAUGAUCCUAAAUAUAUAUGUAGUUUUAUGGUCCUAAAUAUGUAUAAAGCUUUAUGAUCAGAAAUUAUCAAAAGAACAAAAUAGUGAAAAUGGUUAACAGCCAUUUUCAGAAGUUAACAGAAGUUUCUGGACACAUAAACUUGGAUUGGUCCCUGGCUUCACUGCUUCCAAACUCAUUAAAAAAACAAUACCAACCACCAAGUCAUGGGUGAAUGAGGGCAAGAUGUAGUAACACAGGGAAAUGAACAGCCCAAUUCUAUGGCUUAAACCUUUUUGGUCUCAAGAUCUUUUUUACACUCUUAAAAAUUGAGGACCCCAAAGAGCUUUACUUAUGUAUGUCACACACACACACGCCAUAUUAGAAAUUAAAACUAAGAGAUUCCUAAAACACAAGAAUACACAAGGACACAUUUUGCUAGCUUCAAAGAGAUGAAAUCAUUACAUGUCAUGUAGUCUCUGGCCAAUCUAUAUACACAUGAGAGAAUGAGAAUGAAAAAGACAAAUAAUGUCUUAGUUUAUAAUACAAACAGUUUUGACUUCAGACCAAACUCCUCAUGAGACCCACUGGGUUAACACAAUGCCUGGCAGAUAGUAAGUAAUCAAUAUUUGAUAGCAUAAAAAAUAACAGUAUACGUAAUUGAUAAUACGUGUAAAUCUAGGUGAAAAACAAUAGAGAAAAUUAAAUAAAUAACACAAUUUAUCUUUUUUUUUCUUUUAAUUAUGCUCAGAAAGACUAGAAAACAUCCAAAAUGAUAAUGGUACUUACAUAUAGGUAGUUUGACUAAAGUGAUUUUUCCUUCUUACUAUCUUUCUGUAUUUUGAAAAUUUGCUAUAAUAAACAGAUAGUAUUUUCAAAAGGA